GGUUUUGGGACAGUGAGAGAAACUGAAAAUGAACAUUCAAAUACAGGCGUUUUUCCUCUGCUCUCGGGUGUUGGUCUCGGGCGCCUAUGAAUAUUUACAUUGUGCUGCAGAUUGAAGGCGCUUACUGGGAACGCGUUGUCCUGGGUUCUUUCACUACUGCCUGGAGCACAGGCAGACGGAACUCACAGAAGAGCUGGACGGUCCGGCUCUGGCCCGACUGCGUAAUUGUACCGACUGACAUUCUGUGUUUAAUAAUCAAGAAAGCUUUUGAAAGAUAAGUGGUGGUGGAGGAGCCUUUUCCCGAAUUAGUGGAGUGGGAGUAAAAAUUCCAUAGUUUAGAAUUGUCCGUACUUUCCCCAUCCUUUUCUUCUCUCCCAAAUACAAUAAAAUAGGGCUGUGUGUUUCUCUACCUCUGCUCUCCAAACUCGGCUUGUUCUACCCUGGUUUGUCAUCAGAAGCAUGUGGGCCAGCCCUUCCUGCCCCCACCUCUUCUGUGGCACAUGCCAGGAGUCAAGGAGAAAGGUUUUCUGGCAGGUUUUCCUUGAUGUUCCUUUUGAUUAUUGUUGACCAAAGGAGUGAGUGACCAGCUGAGCACCAAGACCCUCAUUCUGAGCACCAGAACCACUGGUGCAGAACCACUCAUUCUGAGCACCAGGACCGCUGGUGCAGAACCACUCAUUCUGAGCACCAGGACCACUGGUGCAGAACCACUCAUUCUGAGCACCAGGACCACUGGUCCUCGUUCAGGAAAGCCCUGAGCUCCAAACUGACGGCCAGGAACAUGCUCUCCCCUUAAAUACACUGUGAGAUGAAGCCUAUAUACUCUUUUUUCUUGGCUCCCUUCAAGAGACUAGAACGUCUUUUUUUUGGUUAUUGUUGUUUUGUUGUUGCGACGGAGUCUGGCUCUGUCGCCACGCUGGAGUGCUGUGGCGUAAUCUCGGCUCACUGCAACCUCCGACUCCCUGAUUCAAGCGAUUCUCCUGCCUCAGCCUCCCAAGUAGCUGGGACUACAGGCGCGCCACCACGCCCAGCUACUGUGUGUGUGUGUUUGAGUGUGUGUGUUUCAGUGUGUGUGUUUGAGUGUGUGUUUAUGUGUGUGUGUAUUUUAGUAGAGACGGGUUUCACCAUGUUGGACAGGAUAGUCUUGAUCUCCUGACCUCGUGAUCUGCCCACCUCGGCUUCCCAAAGUGCUGGGAUUACAGGCGUGAGCCACCGCGCCUGGCCGAGACUAGAACUUCUAGGGGUGUUUCUGACACCAAGGAAAAAGUACAGCGGGCUGUUUAGGCAGGAGAGCUUAGGAGGGGGCCAGGGGCAGCUUUGAAGACCCUUAACGAACGUUCUAAGAUUUUUUGUCUGCCAAUUAACUAAAAGUUAAGUACGUGAUCACAGCAUCGCCUUAUUGAAAUUUCACAUAGUUGAAAGAUGCUCAACUGAGCUACAGCCUCCUUGGGAGAGUCCAUCACUCAAACACAACUCUGAUGGGUCAUGAGUAGCACUCAGGGGACUUGAGGAGACAUUCCCAUCUUCAGAGCCCAGCCAUGACAGCUCUGCAUUUUACUCAGAGCUGGGCACUUGUCAGCCUUAGCAGCUACCUCAUCCUGUUGCUGAGGUUUCCAACCUGUAGCUGAGAUCUUACAUACAGGCCUGUCUCUGUCUGCCCAGGGGCAGAUUGAUGGGACUACUUAGCAUUUUCCAGACAGAGUGGGGGCUAAUCCCAUUGUCCCUACUGGCAGUUGUCAGCUGUGAGAAACAGGCAGCCAAUGUGGUCUGUUAGGGCUGCAGCAUCACCUGCGUUCUCCUAGCGUACCUGGAGAGUGUGUGUUUGCAUCUCUACUGCGGGCAGUACUGCAGCAAAUCCAUCGUUCUUUUGUGUAUUCUCUAUUUUAAUUUCCAUGUGGCUGUGGAAAGGGUUAGAAUUCUGUCUGUACUCCACUUUUCCUGCCACCUCUUUCACAUUGGACAUCCUGGCCCAGGGGGAAACCCUAUUGGAGUAAAGGUAGUAAAAGCAUUAGCGUCUUGGCUAAUCAUUGCUGGCGAACCUAUUCAUUAGAAGCCGUUGGGGGGCUAGGAUCCUUGUGUGUUACCCUUGGAAGAAAUUAAUCAGACAGCAUACCAGGGACACUGUUGUACAUUUUCUUUUGUUUCCUUUAACUUUUAAAAAUAACAUUCUUUUACAUGGGGCAUUGGUUAGAAUCAUCCCAAUGCAGAGCUAACAAGUGUCACUUUUUACUUUGACAGUCGUUUAUCUGGUACUUCCUCUGUGCAAAGCACAGUACUAAAACACGCACCUUUCUGGCUUUGUUGUUAGGAGACAGUGAGGUUGCAUAACCUUGGAGUAUAUAGUCUUCCUUAGUCUUUGUCAGUAUCUCUGUAUUUGCAUUGUGAGGUUUAGUGGCGCAUCUGUCCAUAUACAGCACUGAAUGAGUUACUGCUUUCUAGAUUGGAGACUUUUUGAGCUUAUCACCAUUCUUAACAGGGAUAAUCUAUAAAUAAGUCAGCAUAUCUGGAAUUGGAGGUAAAUUGGAGGAUUAACAGCUCUUCUAUACAUGAGAUAUUUUAUGUACAGAAGUAUUUUAAAAUAUGUAAGGAUAAACUGCCAAAAUUACCUGCACAGUCUUGAAAAAGAAGAGUUCAGAUAUAACUAUAAACUGUAAUUGACAAUGAGUCAUUUGCUUUAAGGGUGCCAACUAUGAAAACAGCCUAGUUAUGCCCCUAAUGAUAAUUAUGAAAACUCUUUCUAGAAGCCAGUUACAUCUCAAGUGAGCUGUAUGUCAGCUUGGAAAAAUAUUUUCUAUUUUACUUAUUUAAAAAUUAUUUGGUGGUGAUGGCUGCACAACACUGUGAAUGUACUUAAUGCCACUAAAUUGCACACUUAAAAGUGGUGAAAAUGAUUUUUUAAAGUAUCCAAUUAAUAGCUGGAGAUGCCAUUUUCCUCCCAUAUAGAGGCAGUUUUCAGAACUCUAAUAUUCAAAUGUUUCACUAAAAUAUUUGCUUUUGUAAUAUGGAGACAAUUUAAUAGAUGAUCACCAAGCAUUGAGAAAGGACAGCUCUCACAAACUUUGAUAGCAAAGAAUGGAAAUAUUACAAGUUUGUUCCUAGCAGCCAGGGGUAACUUGGCAUUUUAUCUAUAAACCCAAUACAUAUUUUAAAGCAAAUGUAAUGCCUGUGAAAAUAAAGGGAAAUUAUAUGCACAUAUGAUAACAGCUUGUUAUUGUUAUAAAUAAUAGCUAACUAUGUACCAGGCAUCUUGGUAAGGACCAUACAUGUGUUAGCUCUUUAUUUUUAUACAAACCAAUGGAACAAGUAUUUCCUCAUAUUGUAGAUGAGGAUGCUGAAAUGUAGGUGACGUUACCAACCUCAGCUCAUGUUGCACAUCUUGAAAGUAGCAGAACUUUCUGAGAAAAAGCAGUCUAUUCCUAGAAUCUCCACUCUUAUUCCCAAGGCAGCCCUGCCUUUUGGAUGUAGUUCUGUGUAAAUCAUUUUGUAAUAUUUGAAUUUGUGAGAUCAGAUUGUUUACUUCUGUGUAGUCUAAAAUUAUUUCAUCAACUUGUGUUUGUAAGUAUGGGCUUUGACAGUGGUGCUGUAAAAAGAAAAUUACACCCCGAAGUGCCGUGUAAAAAGCCAUUGUGUAUGGCCCUUUGUGAUCUGGAGGAAAUAGUCCCCUUUCCACACUCCCAUCUAGUUGGGGUACUCACUCAAUAGCCUGCAUGGCGUCCUUUCUACACCCCACUUACCUGUUCUCGUAUCUGAAGAAAUUUAGUAGUUUUGACCUCUCUUUCACAUCAGAUCGGUAACAGCCCAGCAUGAAAAACAAACGUGAAGUUCCAUAAAAAUGCAACCCACUAAAGUAAGUUGGUGACUGUGUAUAAGGGACAUGUGGCAGAUGUGACAUGGGCAGCGUGUCCUUGGGCGUAUCUCUUCUUUGCUAAAAGUGUCAGAAGCAGAAGAGGUAGGUGAUGGUUUCCAAAGAGUGGCUUAACUAGAAUCUAAGAUGAUAGAGGUCAUUUAAUGUGUUCUCCUAAUUUUACAAAUGAGAAAACUGAAGUCUGGUGAGGCAAAGUGACUUGUCUAAAACUAUAAGCAGUAAAGCUUGAUUUAGGGCUGGAAUCUCAUUUUUCAUAUCUGCUGUUCUUUUCUCUAUUUGGGGGAAAGCCACAUCACCAAGUAGAGCAUAAAUAUGGUGGCCCUGAUUCCAGGGAAAUGAGCUAGGCCAUUAUUAUAUCAUCUCCAAAUGCCCUGUCUUAUCCGUCCAAGGUGCAAGAUGCCUUUUUUGACCCACUGAUUGGUAGGAGACAUGUCCAGACUGGAAAAAGGUUUGGAAGAGGACAGUUGCCCUUUAUUCUGGCGGCAGAUAGCAGCAGGUGAAAAAGUGCUACACAAGUUUGAUGUUUGUGUCUUCUUCUCCAAGGCCAAGAAAUUAUCUCCAUAGGAGGCAACAGUACUAUGCAUGUUAUGAAUUGUGUCUCCUUGGUCAGUGAUAAAGAAAAUGGGAAUAUUGCCACAGCACCUGGAUUCAUGAUUGGGCAGACACCUCCUCCAGCACCUCCUCCACCUCCUCCUCCACCCCCUCCAUCUCCACCAUGUUCAUGUUCAAGGGAAGAGUGUCCUUCCUCCCCUCCUCCACCCCCACCACCUCCACUUCCUGGGGAGCCUCCCAUCCCACCUCCCCCACCAGGCCUACCCCCAACUACUCACAUGAACGGCUACAGCCACCUUGGUAAGAAAAAGCGGAUGAGAAGCUUUUUUUGGAAAACUAUUCCGGAGGAGCAAGUUCGAGGCAAAACCAACAUCUGGACCUUGGCAGCCAGGCAGGAACAUCACUACCAAAUUGAUACAAAGACCAUUGAGGAGCUCUUUGGGCAGCAGGAAGACACCACCAAGUCUUCCCUUCCUAGGAGAGGAAGAACUUUAAAUUCAUCCUUCAGAGAAGCUCGAGAAGAGAUUACUAUUUUGGAUGCAAAACGGAGCAUGAACAUUGGGAUAUUUCUUAAGCAAUUUAAGAAGUCUCCUCGGUCCAUUGUAGAAGAUAUUCAUCAAGGAAAAAGUGAGCAUUAUGGAUCAGAGACCUUGCGAGAAUUUCUUAAGUUUUUGCCAGAGUCAGAAGAGGUAAAGAAGUUAAAAGCGUUUAGUGGCGACGUGUCGAAGCUGUCUCUGGCAGAUUCCUUUCUGUAUGGCUUAAUUCAGGUGCCAAACUAUUCACUUCGGAUUGAAGCCAUGGUGCUAAAGAAGGAAUUUCUACCUUCUUGCUCUUCUCUAUAUACAGAUAUAACAGUUUUAAGAACUGCUAUAAAAGAACUGAUGUCAUGUGAAGAGCUACAUUCAAUAUUACACUUGGUGCUCCAGGCUGGGAAUAUCAUGAAUGCAGGAGGGUAUGCCGGCAAUGCAGUAGGAUUUAAACUGUCUUCUUUGCUCAAAUUGGCAGACACAAAAGCAAACAAACCUGGGAUGAAUCUCCUGCACUUUGUUGCACAGGAAGCCCAAAAGAAAGAUACCAUUCUUCUAAACUUUUCAGAAAAAUUGCAUCAUGUUCAGAAGACUGCUAGAUUAUCUCUGGAGAACACGGAGGCAGAACUGCACUUGCUGUUUGUCAGGACAAAAUCACUAAAAGAAAACAUCCAGCGGGAUGGUGAACUUUGUCAGCAGAUGGAAGAUUUUCUUCAGUUUGCCAUAGAAAAGCUGAGGGAACUGGAAUGCUGGAAACAAGAGCUCCAGGAUGAGGCCUACACCCUUAUAGAUUUUUUCUGUGAAGACAAAAAAACCAUGAAACUGGAUGAAUGCUUUCAGAUAUUUAGAGAUUUCUGUACCAAAUUCAACAAAGCAGUUAAGGACAACCACGACCGGGAGGCGCAGGAGCUGAGGCAGCUGCAGAGGCUGAAGGAGCAGGAGCAGAAGCAGCGCUCCUGGGCAACUGGGGAGCUGGGGGCAUUUGGCCGGAGCAGCAGUGAGAAUGAUGUGGAGCUGCUGACCAAGAAGGGUGCAGAGGGCCUGCUCCCUUUCCUGCACCCCAGGCCCAUCAGCCCCUCCAGCCCCUCCUACCGGCCCCCGAACACCCGCCGCUCCCGCCUCUCCCUGGGUCCCUCUGCUGACCGGGAGCUGCUGACCUUCUUGGAGAGCUCCACCGGCAGCCCUGAGGAGCCCAAUAAGUUCCACAGCCUGCCCCGGAGCAGCCCCCGGCAGGCCCGGCCCACGAUAGCCUGCCUGGAGCCUGCAGAAGUGAGGCACCAGGACUCCAGCUUUGCACACAAACCUCAGGCCUCGGGGGGCCAGGAGGAGGCCCCCAACCCACCCUCAGCACAGGCGCACCAGCUUGCAGCCGCCCAGCCUGAGAACCAUGCCUCUGCCUUCCCCAGAGCUCGGCGCCAGGGCGUCAGUGUCCUCCGAAAGAGGUACAGUGAGCCGGUGAGCCUGGGCUCAGCACAGUCCCCUCCUCUCUCGCCAUUGGCUCUGGGAAUUAAGGAGCAUGAGCUGGUGACAGGGCUGGCCCAGUUCAACCUCCAGGGUUCCCAGGGCAUGGAGGAGACCUCCCAGCUGACUCUGAGUGACUUCAGCCCGAUGGAGCUAGAGUCUGUGGGGCAUAGGGGCCCGCAGUCCCUCAGUGCCAGCAGCAGCAGCCUGACACCCAUGGGCAGAGAUGCCCUGGGGAGUCUCAGCCCAGCGCUGGAGGAUGGCAAGGCUGCCCCCGAUGAGCCUGGAAGUGCAGCUUUGGGAUCUGUGGGUAGCAGCGACCCUGAGAACAAAGAUCCUAGACCUCUGUUCUGCAUCUCGGACACCACCGACUGCUCACUGACCCUGGACUGCUCAGAGGGAACCGACUCCAGACCCAGAGGCGGGGACCCGGAGGAAGGCGGGGAAGGGGAUGGCUCCAUGUCCUCUGGGGUUGGAGAAAUGGGGGACAGCCAAGUCUCCUCCAACCCUACAUCCAGCCCCCCUGGGGAGGCUCCUGCCCCCGUCUCUGUGGAUAGUGAGCCCAGCUGCAAGGGCGGCCUGCCCAGGGACAAACCCACCAAAAGGAAAGAUGUUGUAGCACCAAAGAGAGGCUCCCUGAAAGAGGCGUCUCCCGGGGCCUCCAAGCCCGGGAGCGCCCGGCGGAGCCAGGGGGCAGUGGCCAAGUCUGUGCGGACCCUGACCGCCUCAGAGAACGAGAGCAUGCGCAAGGUCAUGCCCAUCACCAAGUCCAGCAGAGGCGCCGGCUGGAGGCGACCAGAGCUGUCAUCCCGGGGGCCCUCCCAGAAUCCCCCCAGCAGCACAGAUACUGUGUGGUCACGCCAGAACUCCGUGCGGAGGGCCUCCACAGGCGCCGAAGAGCAGAGGCUGCCGCGGGGGAGCAGCGGCUCCAGCAGCACCCGUCCGGGGAGGGACGUUCCCCUGCAGCCCAGGGGUUCUUUCAAGAAGCCCAGUGCCAAACCACUCAGGAACCUCCCCAGACAGAAGCCUGAGGAAAAUAAGACCUGCCGCGCCCACUCCGAGGGCCCUGAGAGUCCCAAAGAAGAGCCCAAGACCCCGUCAGUGCCCAGCGUCCCCCACGAACUACCCCGUGUCCCGAGCUUUGCCCGGAACACAGUGGCCUCCUCCUCUCGAAGCAUGAGAACAGAUCUUCCUCCCGUGGCCAAAGCCCCCGGCAUCACUCGGACAGUGUCGCAGCGGCAGCUGAGGGUGAAAGGGGACCCCGAGGAUGCCGCUCCCAAGGACAGCAGCACUUUGAGGCGAGCCAGCAGUGCCCGGGCCCCCAAGAAGCGCCCAGAGUCUGCGGAGGGUCCCAGUGCCAACACGGAGGCCCCUCUGAAGGCCAGAGGGGCUGGGGAAAGGGCCUCCCUCCGUCGGAAGGACUCCAGUCGGACCACGCUGGGGAGAAUCCUCAAUCCCUUACGGAAGUGAUGGGUGCCUGUCCUCUCCUGCCUCCUGGGAUUCAGACGGUGAAGACUGACUUCUGGGACGAGGAUGGGGAAAGAGGCAGCAUGUCUUUGUUACAGAUAAAGCAGCCACUGGUGCCACUGCUAGUGACGCUGUUGGGAUGGCACAGUCCAGGAGGCCUGUGGACUGCAGCCUGCUGUGCUGAGCCCUGCUGCAGUCCAGCGUCCAGAUGGAUGCACGUUCACUACUGUGACGGCCGCACCUCCCCCAUGCACCCCACCCUCCCCCAAAGCCCGGAUCCCGAGAAAGAUUUAGUAGGAGUGUAAAGUGACAUUCUUAUGAAACAAGUCAAAAAAGUUUUUUUCAGGCCAGUUUUUAUAUAUCAAAGACUUUCUUUUUAAUAUAAAAAUUAGCUAGGUGCAGUGGUUCAUGCCUGUAAUCCAGCACUUUGGGAGGCUAAGAUGAGUGGAUUGCUUGAGCCUAGGAGUUCGAGACCAGCCUAGGCAACAUGGAGAAACCCCGUCUCUAUCAGAAAUACAAAAUUUAGCCGAGUGUGGUGGCACAUGCCUGUGGCCCCAGCCACUCUGAACGCUGAGAUGGGAAGGUCACUUGAGCCCAGGACCCCACCACUGCACUCCAGCCUGGAUGACAGAGUGAGACCUUGUCUCAAACAAAACAAAACAAAAAUGAAAUGUUCUAGUUUUGGUUCCUUUUGCAGAGUGAAAUGCCUCCCAGGAAAAAAAUACAUAUGUAUUUUUUUGCGACAGGGUCGUGCUCUUGUCUCCCAGACUGGACUGCAGUGGCACAAUCAUAGCUCACUGCAGCUUUGACCUCCCAGACCCAAGUGAUCCUCCCACCUCAGCCUCCCUCAGAGCUGGGACUACAGGCGUGCACCACCACGCCUGGUUAAUUGUUUUUUUUUAAUUUAUCUUUUGUAGAGAUGGGAUCUCACUAUGUUGCUCAGGCUGAUCUCGAGCUCCUGGGCUCAAGUGAUCCUCCCACCUCAGCCUCCCAAAGUGCUGGGAUUACAGGUGUGAGCCACCACACUUGGCCAGUAUAUCCUCAGUAUGAAGAUAUUUUUAUCUUCCUGUGUUCUCUGGCUUCAGAGUUUCACCUGCCCACACAGGGUCCGUUGCUGGCAACUGGACUUCCCCAUAAGCCUUGGGUAUCCUGUGAUGGGCUGUGUCUCCCUGAAGAUUGUCUGGCUUGCCCACUUCUCCGUGCAUGACUCUGGGUGUGAGUCUGUCUAGGAACAGGAGGGAAAGUUGGACUCAGACAGAAAUCAGAUGCUUCCAUGUAUUCAGGGCGCGCAUUGUGAGCAGUGGAGUAUGAGCCUUGAGGGCCUCAUGGUUGCAGGGCAGGCUUCCCUGCAGAUGGGUGGCAGCCCCUGGUAGAAUGCUGGAUUUCUCUGGAAUCUAGAAGUGCCAUAUUUUAGUGGAAAGGCAUCAGGGCUGUUUGACAGUGUGCGUCUUUCCAAUCCCAUGUUCCUCCAUUCGUGUGUCUGUUAUAAAACUGAGUGAAGGCUGCUAUGACCUGUGUUCACUCUGGUUACAGGGAGGUGCAAACCAUUCUGUCUCCCAGCCUUUCUUCUCUCUUUGUGUGCUCCCAGCACUUCCUUCUUUUCUAACAUGGCCUGGAGAGAGUCUCUCUCUCCUUGUCUCUGUCUCUUAAUAAUAGUUUUUAACGUGGACAUCUCUUCCUUGGUACAGUGGUUUUUAAAUACUGAGAAGAACCAAGUCAGGUUUUUUAAAGCAGACUAAAAGCAUGAAAUUGCUUUCAGAAGAAUGUAUAUCAUCGGGAAAAGUUCGGGGGCAGAGUGGGGGAAUCAGGCUUUAUUCAAAAGAAACAGUUGAAAACAUGGGACUUUUUCUACCCAAUGCCCAUUUCACGACUCCUCUGAGACUAAUUGGGAAACGGGGAAAUUCUUGGAAUUUUUUUUUUAAGAAACUUUUUUGUGUUUUUUUUAAUUUUAGGUCACUUAUUAGUGAAACCUCAUUUUAGAUCUGACAUUGGUAGAUAGAUGGAUUUAGGCAAAUAUGAUGCGUUUGUGGGGAAUCCACGUGGUUGACGUUAGAACCUCCCUUCUGCAGACUGUUGCCUGUCAUCUAAGCGAAUUGGAAAUGCUGAGCUUCCAUAAGUCAGCUGAGUUUUAAAGGUAAACGUUAUGGCUGAAAUAGUAAAGCACCUGACCACAAAACCUCUUGUAAAAACAGCCCUGAGUAGGUAUUUCCAGGGCUCCACAAAGUUGCUUAUGGGAAUCCUGAGCUGCUUUUCACCAUCUCAAGAAGCCUAAGAAGUUAUAUAUUUAAUCAGGUAGACAAAACAGUUCAAAGCAUAAGGUCCAUGGUGGUGGAAAAUGGAUGCAAGUGAUUCUAAGUUUGUGGAUUUGUGGAUAGCAGAGGGAUCGGGACCUCUUGGAGGAACCCUGGGUACCAAGCUCCCAGGCCCUUCCUCUAUCAUGGAUGCUGGGUGACUUUGGGAAGUCACCACCUCUUCCCAAGCCUGUUUCCCAUAUCACAGAUGUGGGGCCAUGGCCUCGAUGAUGGUCUCCACAGGUCUUUCCACCUCUGUGAGUCCAAGUCAGGUCAAUCAGCAAGGACCCAUCUCUGCCCUGGGUCAGCUCCUCAGAACCAACCCCCAGCAUCUCUAAAGCAAAAGCCUCACCUCAAGGGCUGCUCAGAAGAGAGCACCUUCAGCAUGAGUUGUUGCUGGAAGAUCUAAUAAGCUGUGUUUCCUGGGAAGUGGUGCUUUACUUAGCCCUGUGGACAACUUCUCUAUGCAUCUGUGUGAGCAGAUGAUCAUUGUAUUACCUUUUAUCGGUAGUAAGCUUGGAAAAAUAAUUUAAGAAUACAAUGGAGAAAUGUAAAUAAGUAUCUAUGUAAAUUUGUUUAAAAUAAACUGAAUGUAUUUAAUGGUCCAUUUAUAUGUUCUUUUAUGUAACAUGUAGUUUAAUAAAGUUCCUGUUUAUGAGA